AGUGCCUUGUCAGUUAGUCAUCCAAACAAAACAGAUGAAGUAAUGCUCUGCAGUUCCCCAGGGGCAUGUUUAAGAAAAGAGCUGCCAGACUCCAUCAACAGCUUACUUUCUGGUGAUGUCGGAGCACAAAAUUGAAAAAUCAGGAGUCGCCAGAGAAGAAAGGGAGAUUAAUUUCAUACAGUUUAUAAAAAGGACACCUGUUGUGGGAAAAACAGUUUGUCAUCUUCAUCUCAAUGUACAAAUUGCCAAAGAGAAGAAAUAAAAAGGAAAGUGUUGAGCCAGUGAGAAUGGGUGUGUAGAGGAGGAUGGGUCGAGCGGACCUUUCUCAGGGAUCCAGUACAUUCUACAAGGAGGAGAAGAAGCUGAGUUCAUGUGUUGGAGUAAGCUGUGAGUCAUGACUUGAAAGACUGUUGCUUACUGCCCUUCAUUGACUAAAUAUUUCUUCCCAGAAACCACCUGCAGUAAAUUCAAAGCAGCUAUGUUUCUGCCUCAGUGCGGGAUUUCUGGGAACUGAGUUUAUGUGCAGUCAGUCCCAGAAAUCAUGGAACGGUGGGUGAGAUCUUAGGAUUUCAUUUGCUGUUCUGUAUUUUUCUUUUCUCUCUCUCUUUCUCUCUCUCUCCCCCUCCCCGCCUCCCUCCCUGUGUCUCCCUCUCUCUCCCUGUCUCCCUCUCUCUCCCUGUCUCCCUCUCUCUCCCUGUCUCCCUCUCUCUCCCUGUCUCCCUCUCUCUCCCUGUCUCCCUCUCUCUCCCUGUCUCCCUCUCUCUCCCUGUCUCUCUCUCUCUCCCUGUCUCUCUCUCUCUCUCCCUGUCUCUCUCUUUCUCUCUUUCUUUCGAGACAGGGUCUUGUUCUUGCCCAGGCUGGAGUGCAGUAGUAUGAUCUCGGCUCACUGCAGCCUCCAUCUUCUGGGCUCAAGUGAUCCUGCCUCAGUCUCCUAAGUAGCUGAGACUUUGAGCAUGUGCCACGACACCCAGCUAAUUUUUGUAUCUUUUUUUGUAGAGAUGGGGUUUCGCCAUGUUGCCCAGGCUGGUCUUGAACUCCUGGGCUCAAGCGAUCCACCUGCCUCAGUCUCCCAAAGGCUUGAGAUUAUACACAGGAGCCACUGCACCCAGCCUGUUCUGUGUUUUUCUACAUUAAAUGAUGACACGGAUAUUACGUCGCUGACUUGGGGAGACAGUCUCAGUUUCAUAUAUUAUGUUCUGUACUGCCCAUAAACAUCCUCAUGCUUGUUAGAUUGUGUUCUGGAAAAUUUGGCCUCUGUAUUUCUAGCAACCCUUUCUAUGAUGACACAUUUUAGCAAGAAAAAAAAUCAUAAUUUGCUUAUUAAUAUUUUAAUGGAGAAGGGCUUUUGAUAUUAGAAAACUGGGAAUAGGCCGGGCGCUGUGGCUCACACCUGUAAUCCCAGCACUUUAGGAGCCCGAAGCAUGCGGAUCACGAGGUCAAGAGAUCGAGACCAUCCUGGCCAACGUGGUGAAACCCUGUCUCUACUAAAAAUAUGAAAAUUAGCUGAGCGUGGUGGUGCACGCCUGUAGUCCCAGCUACUGGAGAGGCUGAGGCAGAAGAAGCGCUUGAACCCGGGAGGCAGAGGGUGCAGUGAACUGAGAUCACGCCACUGCACUACAGCCUGGCGGCAGAGUGAGACUCCGCCUCAAAAAAAAAAAAAAUCUGGGAGUAAAAAGUCAUGACUAGGGGUAGUGAGAAUGACUGCUAAUAGGUCAAACAUUCUGAGGAAAGUUUUUGAGCUAAUGGAGAUGUUUUGGAAUUAGAUAGUGAUGAGGCUGGAAACGGUGAUUUCUGCCUGUAAUCCCAGCAUUUUGGGAGGCCAAGGUGGGAGAAUCUCUUGAGCCCAGCAGUUUGAGACCAGCCUGGGCAACAUAGUGAGAUUCAGUAUCUACCAAAAAUUUAAAAUUCGCUGGGCUUGGUGGCGUGCACCUGUAGUCCCAGCUGUUCAAGAGGCUGAGGUGGGAGGAUUGCUUGAGCCUAGGAGUUUGAGGCUGUAGUGAGCCAUGAUUGUGCUACUGCACUCUAGCCUGGGCAACAGAGCGAUGACACGCUGUCUCUUAAAUAAAUAAAUAAAAAUAAAGAACAAAAAGUCAUGGCUAAAUGUGUGAUACAUUUCAGAUUUUGAAAUAGCUUCAGUUAUUGAGUGUUUACUAUGUAUAAGCCACUUAAUUUUCCUACCCCUUACAAAGUAGGCAGUGAUAACAUUAUACCUGAGGAAAUGGAACUCAGAGAGGUUUUUUAACUUGCCCCAGCUCAGGUGGCUAUAGGGACAAGGUUACCACGCGCACAGUGGGUUCUGCCGGGGGUGGAAUCCGCCUGUGCUGGUGUCUCCUACUCUGACGUGCGUCUCUUAUGGAGGAAUUUGACUCAGUUUUUUCUACUCCCACUCCCCCUCUCCCUUUUUUUGGUGUUAGAAAAAGUGAAAUCACCUCUAUUUGAAGGAGGGGAUUGUGGAUAAGAUUUGACCAGGUUUCAGUUGUGAUUUGAUGGCAUAUUUGGAAAUUUUGUGGAAAAACCUGGGUUAACUUUUCAGGAAAUCGCAGUCAAAAAAAAAAAAAAAGAGAGAGAGACUUUGCUUCCCUGUAGAUUGUUUCAGUCCUGGUGGUGUCUUUUGAGAUAGUGAAGAGCAUAGCUGAAAAAGUGGAAACUGAUGAUGCUUUAGCUUUUAUUGUUUUUUAAACAUUCUGGGAAAGUUGAAGGGAGAGGCAACUUUCUGCUAUGCUUCUCCUGAAAGUGAUAUUAACAUUAAAAAUCGGUGUCAUUGUUUUUCUGCUAGUGUGAGCUUUAUAUUUUUUUUCUUUUUUUUUUUUUGAGAUGGAGUCUUGCUCUGUUGCCAGGCUGGAGUGCAGUGGCACGACCUCGGCUCACUGCAACCUCCAUCUCCUGAGCGAUACUCCUGCCUCAGCCUCCCGAAUAGCUGGGAUUACAGGCAUGCGCCACCACACCCAGCUCAUUUAUUUUUGCAUUUUUAGUAGAGACAGGGUUUUACCAUGUUUGCCAGGAUGGUCUCCAUCUCUUGACUUCCUGAUCUGCCCGCCUCGGCCUCCCAAAGUGCUGGGAUUACAGGCGUGAGCCACCGCGUCCGGCCGAGCUUUAUAUUCUUGAAUAUUGGAGUCACCUCUGCUCACCAGCAUAUAGACCGAGACAUAGAGUAUGUUGUUAGACUCUAAAACAGAAACGGCAUUAAUUUGCAUAAAAUCGCAUAUGCUCUGUUGCAAUAAUUUUCAUUGUGCCUGUUUUAGAAUUGAGUUGACACUUCAUACAGAGUAUUCCAACUCAAUUAAAAAAGAGACAUCGCAGAAGAAUUUGUGUGGCUUUGAAAUUUAUUUUGGGCACAGUCCCUGAAAGAAAUGAGCCUCUAAGGACUUUUGUUCUUUGUGGUGUUUUGAAACCUUCUCGCCAGUUAUAUACAUUAAGAACACGUAGAGCAGGUUGGGGUUGGUCUGCUGGGUAGAAUGCCUGCAAAGGGACCAGAGGUCUGUCAGAACAAGAGUCUCUUAGUGCAGUGCCUCCCGCCGGGGGGUGACCUUUUCAUGAUGUUUGGACUGUCAUCUUUGUUUCCCAGUUUCAAAUGCCUAGCUCAGAAUUAUUUAGUGCUUGAAGUGGUUUUCAUCUUCAAAGGACGUUAUGGACAUUAUUUAAUAUACAUGACACUGUGUAAUGAAUGAGCUGUUUAUCCCUUGAGUAACGUCAACAUGCCAGGUGCCAUACAGCUGGAGAAGACAAAAAUAAUACUCUGUCCAGUGGGAGCUGAUAGUCUAAAGAGGCAAGAUGAUUAGGCAGAUUCUCUCUUUUGGCCUCUUUUAAAAAUGUGCUGGGGAAUAAUGUAGAAAUUAAAAUUAUAAAAGAUGAUCAACUAGCUCAAGUCUACCUAAUUGAAAUUGCCCUCAAGGUGGAAAUGAAAUUUGAGAUGCUCUUAAAAAGACAUCAUGUGUUAGCUCCCAUUUAUCACACAUUUACUGGUACACGCCUAUUUUACUUGUGUUACAGGUGAGGAAUUUGGUGAAGACCAGUGCAGAAUUAUUCUCAGAUCUCCUUCCCGACUCGUCCCUUUCUCCCACUGAAGCUCCUCUUUUUGUUUGCAUGGUCUAGGAUGGCACUUUGUAACCAAGGCCACAUGUGAUGCCCAAACAUACAUUUAUUAUUUUUUUUGAGAUGGAGUCUUGCUCUGUCGCCCAGGCUGGAGUGCAGCGGUGUGAUUUUGACUCACUCUAUCUUCUGCCUCCUGGGUUCAAGCGAUUCUCCUGCCUUAGUCUCCUUGUAACUGGGAUUACAGGCAUGCGCCACCACACCCGGCUAAUUUUUGUAUUUUUGUAGAGAUGGGGUUUCACCAUGUUGGCCAGGCUGGUCUUGAACUCCUGACCUCCAGUGAUACACCUUGGCCUCCCAAAGUGCUGGGAUUACAGGUGUGAGCUACCAUGCCUGGCUCAAACACACAUUUCUUAGUUGCAGAUCAGUCUGUCCUUUGUAGCUGGGCAGACCUCCUGGGAAACUUGGACUUCUUGCCCCUGUUGGCCUGUGUGUCUUGUGCUCUUGUACCUGUACCUCUUUGUGUUUGCUGUUCCCUCUUCUUCCUGGUUUCCCUUCCUAACUCAGCUCAAACAUCCUUUCCUUUGGAAAACUGCACUUGACCAUCCUGUCCCAGCCUCUUGAGGCCCAUUGGUGUUGGCAUGACACUUUGUGAGAACUGGAUUCUGGACUGGUUCCUUUGGGUUAUAAUUGUUCCUUCACUCGUGAGUUUGAGUUGCUGGGACCUCUGACCCCAGCGCCGGCCCAGAGCAGUCCCCAGGUAGAAGUGCAGUAGAUGGUUGUUGUGAUUUAUGCCUGUGGUUCCUUAACUCAGAUUUUAGCAUAAUUACCUGGAAAGUUUUCUUUAAAAAUACAGAAUCCCUAGAGAUUCUGAUUUAGUGGUUCUAGAUUAGGCCCCUAGAAAUGUAUUUUGAAAAAACUCUACUUGUAGUUUGUUUUGAGACAGCGUCUCACCCUGUCACCCAGGCUAGAGUUCAGUGGUGUGAUUAUGGCUUACUGCAGCCUUCACCUUGUGGGCUCAGGCGAUCCACCCACCUUAGCCUCCUGAGUAGCUGGGAUUGCAGGUGCAUACCACUAUGCCUGGCUAGUUUUUUGUAGAAAUGGGGUCUUGCCAUGGAGGCCAGGCAGGUCUCAACCUCCUGGACUCCAGCCAUCUGCCUGUCUUGGCCUCCUGAAGUGCUGGGAUUCCAGGUGUGAACCGCCAUGCCUGGUCUCUACUGGGAAUUUAGACGCACAGCUAGGGUUAGGAACCACCGAGUUAUGCCAAGGCACAGUAUUAGUUGUGGGUUAUGGAAUCACGGCCAAUUUGGAGUAAGGUGUAAGUGCAGUUUGCAGAAUCAUUCCAUUCACAUAUCUGGAGAGAGUGGAGAAAAUGAAUGCAGUCCCUUUAUGAUGAGGAUGUGCUCCAUGAAGGAGAAGAUCCUGGCUCGUGGAGGAGCUUCCUGCUCUGUGAACAUACUGAAGGCACAAUUGGCCCUUCAAACUCUCAUUUGAAGUCACUGUGUUGCCAUAGAGAUAUUGUGUAGUGUUGAAGGAGAUUAGAGAAAUCAUGUCGUAAAUUAUCAGAACAGAUGGCUUGUAAUUUAACACUCUUCUAGCCCAUAUUCUUUGUACUGACCUUGAGAACAUUGAAGGUAUCAGUUUUUACUUUGUUCUUUUACCUAUAAAAAUGGCAGAGUUCAUAUUGAGUGAGAUCUAAAAUGGGUAUUAGAUAUGCCACAUACACAGUGUGGUAUGUGAAAGCAUUUUAGGAGUGGCUUCCUUAACUUUGCUUGUAUAUUUUCCCCUCAGUUCCCUGGAUAUAUAGAAUAAUGAGCCUGUCUUCCUUAUUAUUUUGAUAGCACUGGUCAGGGAUCAUUUUUAUAUCCUGGCUUGAUGAUAAUCGUAUUCCUUUGCAAGUGCAGUUCUGUUUGCAAGUAUUAUAUGAUCAUGUAGAUUCAGGCAGCAUAAUCACUUCCAAGGUGUUUUUAUAUGUCAUCAACCACAUAAAGGGUAUUUUCUUUUUUUUUCUUCUCUUUUGAGACAGUGUCUCUCUCUCUUGCCCAGGCUGGCAUGCAGUGGCACGAUCUUGGCUCACUGCAGCCUCCACCUCCCAGGUUCAAGUGAUUCUCCUGCCUCAGCCUCCUGAGUAGCUGGGAGUACAGGUGUGUACCACCAUGCCUGGCUAAUUUUUAUUUUUUGUUUGUUUGUUUUUUUGUUUUUUAAAUUUUACUUUAAGUUCUGGGAUACAUGUGCAGAACGUGCAGGUUUGUUACAUAGGUAUACACAUGCCGUGGUGGUUUGUUACACCUAUCAACUCAUCGUCUAGGUUUUAAGCCCUGCAUGCAUUAGGUAUUAGUCCUUAUGCCCUCCCUCCCUUUGCCCCCCAUCCCUGGACAGGCCCUGGUCCGGUGUGUGAUGUUCCCCUCCCUGUGCCCAUAUCUUCUCAUUGUUCAACUCUUACUUAUAAGUGAGAACAUGUGGUGUUUGGUUUUCUGUUCCUGUGUUAGUUUGCCAAGAAUGAUGGCUUCCCACUUCAUCCAUGUCCCUGAAAAGGAAAUGAACUCAUUCUUUUUUAUGGCUGCAUAGUAUUCUAUGGUGUAAAUUUUGUAUUUUUAGUAGAGACGGGGUUUCACCAUGUUGGCCAGGCUGGUCUCGAACCACCUGCCUCAGCUUCUUAAAGUGCUGGGAUUAUAGGUGUGAGCCACCAGGCCUGGCCAACUAAAGGGUAUUUUCUAAAAGGAGACUUCUUUGAAAUUUUUUCUGUCUCUCUAUUCUAGCCUGGGUCUGAUGUGUAAGUCUUAAAAGAUUGUAUCCUUCAUUAAGGACAACUAUUGCCUCUUGCAGGGAGCUGCAUCCUGAUUGGGAUUCUGGCACAUUCACACAUGCACAUUGUUGUAGAUGACCAGAGUAGAUAUGUACCUAAAACAUUUCAAAUUAACAAAAUCAUAAUCCUGUGAGUGUAAUUUAAAAAUCUAAUAAAGCUUACCUUAUUUUUAAAGUACUUGUAGUUAGACAUAUAUUAACACAACUAUUUCAUAUGGUUUUAUUCUCACAUGCUUGAAGUAUUCAGGAAUCUUAAAUAGGCUCUUCAUACAUUUUCAUGAGCCUCAUUUCUUAUGUGUCAUACAGUAGGAAAUUAAGUAAGUUUUCCGAUCUCCAGAUAAUUCCUGAGUUGCUCUUGUGUGAAUGUGUGUUUUAACUGAAUCCAGACAUUCAUAGUAGUGAGCACUUUCUUUGACUCCUUUUUUACUAGCCUACACUGCUUAUACUAAUGGGGGUUUCUGAUGCCACUCAGCAGUGGGACAGAGAGGUCAGUUGUGAGCCUGACCCUGUUGGAUAUAGCAAUUUUUACCUCAGGAUGACACAUUCACGUGACUUAAAUUCUUUGACACUUCUGUGUCAAUGCUAGAAAAUUUUUUAUAAAAGUGCUAGGUAAUUAUAUCAGAAAGCAUCUGAAAAACAGUCUUAUCAGAAGGGCUUAGAGCCAUUACAGGAGUGAGGGAAAUAGUGUGGAAAUAAGCUAUAAUUUCCUUGAUGAGCAUGUCAUACUACAAGACAAGGUUGGCUCAACCUCCUGGUAACUGUCCUGCCCCAGAAUGGGCUAGCUCCAGCUUAAAUAAAUUGGAAUCAGAUUACCUGGGUAUUGAAUUGCAUGGCUUCAGGAGAGGGUGUUUGGUUCUGUAAAGCCACAUGUCAUGGUAGUGAGGUGAGACUGAUGGUAGUAUUUGUUCAAGAAUCCGAUUUUCAUUGAGGGCACAAAGGCUCUGUUGUGCCACGCUCAGGAUCUUGUUUUCCUGAGAUUGCUUCAGGCAGAUUUAAACAAUGGCCUCUCAACGUACUGGAUUUAAAGAGUAAGUAGUUCUCCAUGAUCUUAUUUCUCAUUAGUAGGGAAAUGUAAACUUUUACCUUUGGUCAAAAUUUUGCUCCUGUCACCUGACCCCCUGAUGUCAUUAUGAUUGUCUUUUCCUUGCAGUAUUGCCUUGUCAGUUACUCUUGCCAGAGGGAUUUCAUCAUUGGAGUAUCUGCAUGUCUAAGUCCAAUUCAGCUCUUUACAUAUAGGCCCCAUGCCCUAAGUGUUGCUGUCAUUUUGCCUGUUUAGUUACUUUACAAACACUAAUGGCACGUAAGGCUCCUGGGAACCCUGGGUCUGGAACAGGCACAGGCCACAGAACAGAUGGCCCUUGCCAGGUGGUCCUUGGGUGCACAGUGGCUGUGGAGCUGCUGUCUCUCAACAAAGGAAGGAAGGGCACUCUCAGGGAAAUCAAAUGGAUCAAAGCCGUCCCCUUACCCGUGUUGCCCCUUUAAGCCUUCCCAGUAGCUCUACUUUUAUUUUUAUUUUAUUUCAACUUUUAUUUUAGAUACAGGGGAUAUACGAGCAGAUUUGUUAUGUGAGAAUAUUGCUUGAUGCUAAGGUUUGGAAUAUGGAUCCCGUCACCCAGGUAGUGAGCAUAGUACCUGAUGCGUAGUUUUUAAACCGACACCCUCACCCUCUGGUAGUCCACAGUGUCUAGUGUUCCUGUAUUUACGUCCAUGCAUCCUUAAUGUUAGCUCCCACUUAUAAGCGAGAACAUGCAGUAUUUGGUUUUCUGUUCCUGUGUUAAUUAAGAUUAUGGCCUCCAGUUCCAUCCGUGUUCCUGCAAAAGACAUGAUUUCAUUCUUUUUUAAUCAAUGCGUAGUAUUCCAUGGUGUAUAUGUACCACCUUUUCUUUAUCCAGUCUACCAUUGGCGGGCACGUGGGUUGACUUCAUGUCUUUGCUGUUGUGAAUAGUGCAGCUGUAUUUUUAUUUUAUUCUUCCUGUUGACCCUCUGUCUGUCUUUCUGAGGCUCUGUGUCUCUGUGGACCCUUCAAAGGGACUUUCCUUUGUUUAGGAGAGUGACUCAUCCUGAGGUCAUUCUCAACCUUUCCUUGGGAAGGGAUGUAGCCCUUCGCAGACAGAGCUGCAUUUGCCCAGAAGUAAGCAUUUUCACAAAGGCCCCUGGAUCCCAGGUGCCCUCCUGCACAGUGAACUCUACCGGUGGUGUCAUUCUUAGCCUUGUGGGUCUGGGUUUCCCAGCCUCCAGAGGUAGGAACGCCAACCAUCCUGGGAUGGUAGGUGGCCGCUAGGCCCAGAUGGACUGCAUCCAGACCUGCUGAGUGAAUGAAUGCCUUUCUUCUGUAAAUGGACUCCUUAUCAUUCUGUUUUAGCUCCUCUUUUUCUCAUUUCUUCCUUUCUCCUGCAUUUCUCUUGUUUCUCAUUCUUCUUUGACCACUUAAGAGUGACGGUGUCACUCAUGGCCAUUGCCCAUUGCUAAACUGUGCUGGAGGCAGUUAGAGAUGAGUCUGAUUUGUGGGGCAGGAAUUUAGGGGGAUGCUCCCGGUGGAGAGUCUGUUGGAUUCUGCAUUAGCACCUCACUACAGACUUCACCUGGGGGUAAGCCGUGCCUGGGGGGCACCCCCUUCUUUUCUGCCCCAAGGCCCUGGGUCUGAGCCUGUCUUCUUCUGCAUGUCCCCUUCCUGUCUCUCAGUCGUCCCGUCACUUAGUGGGGUCUCUUGACACUUAAUUCUCUUACUGCUUGAUCCCAAUCCCCUUUAAGCACAGUUUUGUCUGAUUUAAAAUUUGCAUUUUAUGGUGAUCUUAAUAGAUUUGGCUUAGCAAAUAAGUGUGAUGCUUCUUAAUUUCGGGGUAAUUUAAUCCCUUUUUCUAAAUUGUGGUAUAUUAUUCCUUAAAAAUUGUUUUGGCUCAGUUGCCCUGGUGUCAUGUGAUUUCUUCUUGACGUUUUCUUUUCCGAGCUGCAGUUCAUGUUGAGGUUAACUCCUACUCAUCCCUCUGCCCCGAGUGCUCAGCACAUAGUCAGUGCUUAGUAAGUGUUCACCAAAAGCAAGAACAAGCGCUUGCUGCAUCCCCAAGUCCAGUGGCCAGUUUCCCUGUCUCAGGAGGCUGGUGGGACGUGGUAACUAUUGAGCCAGCAAAACUGGGCCAGAGGCUGGGCCAUUUUAUGGUGUAAUGUCCUCUCCAGUAGAAAUUCAUGAGAGGGGAAAAAGGAGAAAGGGAGACGGUAGAUUCUUACGGAUGAGGUGUGCGUGUCUGUGGAAUAUGGGCAUAGGCAGCAGUGGAGAAGGGAGGUCUCAGCAAAAGCAGCUACCCCUGUUUGUUGGGCUGUGUUCACUUGGCAAGUUGCUGUGGAUCUAACUGCUGUUCACUGUUAAUAAUUAGUCCUCAAGCGCCCAUUCUUGGGCUUAUGUCUUCUGCACAAUUCCUCAGUCUCUAGAUUGACCAGGCUCCCCGUGGACCCUAAUUAAUAUUUUCUGACCGAUCACUGGGUUUGAUCAGUCAAUGGAGGGUGAAGAAGCAUCCAUUAUCAGGUUUCCUUUGAGAUUUAAGAUCUAGUUGCCUCUGGUGUUUCUAUUAUGUGUUAAUGAGUUGAUUUCUGUUUCCUAAUGAUUAGGCUGUGGAACAGUAACUCUGGGGGGAAGAUGGCAUUGGUAAGAUUUGCUAAGUUCUUGGGUAUAUUUUUACAGGAGUAUGUUCCAUGAGCCCGUUAAGAAUGUUCCAGGUCUUGCCCUGUCUCCCCAUUUCCAUACUUCACUUCCAUUUUUAGGACUUCUCCCCAGCGUCAAAACUUUAUUUACACGAACCUGAAAGCAGGCUGCAGGGCUGUUUGAAAUCACACACGUCAAUAUGAGGCCAACCCAGUUUUUCAUAAAUAGGUCAGAUUGUUUCUAUAAAGCAGGAUUCCAAAAACAGUCUUGUUAAAGAAAAAGUAUUUUAAGAAAAGAUACCCAUUGUUUAAAUCUUAACCCUAUUGCCUAGGGCUUGGGAUAAUACUAGUACUAGAAAAUGCUGAUUUCUGGGGCCUGCCUUGGAAGAACUGAGACUUGCCCCAGACAUCAUGAAGAGAAAGCUUGCAGGCCACAUGUACUAAGAUCCGGGGAUAGGUGUGAGUCAGAGGCUGGGCAAGGGCCUCUAAGGAGCUCUUGGUGCCCUUGAAGAGGAGCAUGGUUCUGGGUGGAUGCACCAUGAAGGGCUGUUACUGGCAGCAUUCACUAGUCCCCCUGACCCACCACCAGUGGAACAAGUACCCUUGCUUUACCUAAAUACUGAACAUUCAUUUCUUACUUAGUAGAGAUUGACUUAAAUCUCUUUUUUUUAAAUUGUGCUUUUUAAUCUAUAUAUCAGAAUCAUCUGAUAAUUGUGUGAUACUGAGGAGGUAUUUAAGCCAUAGCAAAUCAGGAAGGGAAGAAGCUAAGAUGGGGUUUACAAGAUAGUUCUUCACAUGUGUCUGAAAUUAGUACUCUUAAGAAUGUUACUAAUUUCUGGCAGGAUCCCUGGAAAAGUUUCUAGAACAAUUGGAAGAGAAGCCAGAAUAGCUGUGAAAAAUGGCGGUGUUCACAGGUGUAAAUACUCACAGCCUCACACUCAAGUGUGUCAUCCUGAAAUCAGUGAAAUGCUCUCACUGAUUUCAUGGACCUUAUCAUCCGUGAGAACUGGAUAUGCCACGUGUUUAAUUCAUGACUGAGUUUUAUGUGCUGUUCACACAGCCUAAUGCAAGACAUUCACUUGAAGAAGUUUACCCUGAAAUCCCCCAAAUAGGGAGGUCCCACGUAGGUGAACUAAAUAGGCUCUCUACAAGUACAUUACUCAUAUUUUUAAAAUAGGAGAUUCCCAAGUGGAUCUGGCUAUUGGCCAACAGAAUGAGACUUACACAGCCUGAUAUAAAUCGGUUCAUUUCUCCUUGUACUGUAGUUGAUUUUCAGGAGGAUUGAUGUGCAAUUUAUUGUUUGUCUGCAGCAGAAUGACUUGUAUGGCUCUGGGUGCUGUUUUCUAGUGCUGUGUUUGUGGUGCAUGUCUUCUUCCUGUUUCUUCUGAUUCUGAGUUCCGCCCUUUUUAGCUAGCAUUCAGUUGGUCUGGCUUUAUUUGACUUCUUUGACUUGGUGAGUGCCAUGGUUUGUGAGUUAUACUAUCAUUUGUGGUUUAAACAUUUCAGUUUUUGUUACUAUAUGUCCAUCUAUGUGGCCAUCUUCUCAUUUUAAUUACCAAUACAUGUUUCAGCUUGCUUUUUGGAAAAAGUGUUGAGAUGCAAAUGUGUCUUUGGAAGUGUCACUGAGAAACCCAAGGUCUAUCUGGCAUUCCGCUCCUGGCGGCAGACCGUAGUCUUUGUCCACGGGUUGGGAAGAGAGCUGUGAAACAGGGAGGCCUUGCCGACUGUCCUACCUGCAAUCUGGACUUUGCACAUGGAGCCUCUACUUAGGGGAUUAGUUUUUUGACUACUGCUGUUUGAUUUUUGCUUUUUAAUUGGGUUAUUUGAGGUGAAUGCAUGGUUUAGGUUUCUCGUUCUUUGUGUUGGACAGAAUUAAAGGGAAAUUUGAGACAUCCUGGUCUACUUAUGUUCAACUCCGUUAUAUUCUUUUUUAAUGGGCAAUAAAACUGCCUUUUUUUUUUUUUUUUACUUUUCUCUUUUUUAGAUGGAAGGUUCCCCAUUUUUAUUUUUACAUCACGUUCUUCCUCAUACAGUUUUCUUCAACAGUACCAAGAGUCGUAUUUUUAAGAAAGUGUCUCUAAAUUUUCUUUGCUUUUGUAGGACUAUGUCAUUUCUGAUGAUCAUUAAUUGGUAUGCCUAACUCUCCCCUUUGACCCAGGUAUUACUAAUAUUGACUGAAAGAUGGAAAAUUUCAAAGAUGGAAAAUUUGGAUUACUGCUGUGUCUUUACCAUUGAGUCCCAGGAAAUAACUUGCCCAGUUUCAUAAAUUCUUAGACGUUGGUUUCUCUUGUGAUUGUCAAGUCUUUGGUGUUCUUUACUUUAUUCACCUGGACCACUUGAGUUGUUAUUCAUCGAACACACACGUGUGUGUGACAUGAAGUAUAACUUGUUCACCCUUACUUUGUGCAGUGGUGGUAAUAAAAUUGUUUUAAACCUCUUAAUUAUGGUUUUUCAUGUUGGAUUCACUGUGAGUUCUUAAAAAAAAGGAUCACCCACUGAUGGAUUCAAAUCUACCUUUGGAAAAUUAAAGUGAUAAGCACUUAAUGGCAUUUUGGGAUUAGCUUGAGAAUAUCUGUAAGUUGAUUGUACUUGAAACAUGCAGUUGUGUUGUGACCAUCUGUAGAGUGAUGUGGUAAUUAGGCAAAGCAUUUUAGAAAGGCUUUAUUACUAAAAACAAGUGGUAGCUAGUUUUCAUAGGCAAAGGAGACAGUCUUUUAGAAAAGUGGUGUUCCAGGUGAUUUAAUGGAAAGCCAAUGAAAUUGGGGAGAGGGAGAGGGAGAGGGAAAAGGUGAAAGAAGUUCUGAAGUCAGGCUGCUUGGCAGGCACCGAGGGAAUUGACUGAUGGAGCUCAUCUGUAAUCCUGGGAUGCGUUUUCUGUGUUUUAUCCAAACCAGCGAUUUUUGUUAUAACAUGUUUGGAAAGCCUUUUUUUCUUUUUUGGUAAGUUUCCUACUAGACAUAUAAAAAAGACUUAUAAAGUUCUUUGUGAGAGCUUUAUAAUAUAGAUAAUAUCUAGCUUUUUUCUUUCGUAAUUAAAAAAUUCAAUGGAGAGAUUAUAGUAGUUUGUAUAUACUGUAGUUAGAAAGGUUUGGUUUUGUUUAAAAUUGUUGUACAUUUGCUUUUGGUAAUCUUUAGUUGCUUGAACCCUCCACCCUUCAGUUUAACUUUUAUUUAAAACAAUCUUUGAUUCUUAUUCAUGCAUUGAACAUUGGCUGAGAACCUGCUAUGUGCUAAACAGUCACUAAAAGUGAAGCUUCUCUCUCUUUUUUUUUUUUUUUUUUGGAGAAGUCUUGCUUUGUCGCCUAGCCUGGAGUGCAGUGGUGCAAUCUUGGCUCACUGCAACGUCCACCUCCUGGGUUCAGGUGAUUCUCCUGCCUCAGCCUCCCGAGUAGCUGGGAUUACAGGCGUGCUCCACCAUGCCUGGCUAAUUUUUGUACUUUAGUCGAGACGGGGUUUCACCAUGUUGGCCAGCGUGGUCUGGAACUCCUGACUUCAGUGAUCCUCUCGCCUUCGCUUCCCAAAGUGCUGGGAUUACAGGAGUGAACCUCUGUGCCUGGCUCGAGAUGUAAUAUAUUCUCUUGAAAGAUAAUAUUACAUCUAGGGAACUAUCUUUAUCACUUUAUUUAACUAUUUACAUUGAAAAUACUAGAAUAAAAUAUAAGUACAUAUUUGUUUUUAACUUAAUAUACAAUUUCAGUGUUAGAUGAAAUGAAGAUGGAAUAUUAACAAUGUAUAAGUAAUGAAAAAUUACUGAAACUUGACUCUGUUUUAGCAUUCCAAAUCUUAAAUUAUAUUCCUUGCCCUAAAAUAAAAUAUCAUGAAGAUAUUUUGGGUGAACAGUUGGAAAUUGUUACAAUUCUAGAGUAUUAAAGAUACCAAGAACAUUCAGAGGAUCCAGCCGAACCUGACUUGCCCAAGAAAAUAAGUAAAUCAUUUAGUUUGUCACUUCAGUUUGCAUGACCACAAAGAACUGUACACGCAAUGAGUUAUUACAUUGUUAUAGAAGAAACAAAAUAUUUUAUAAUAGUUUGCCAAAAAUAUCAUGCCAUUAUGAGAAAAACCUGUUGACUAAGUCGGCCUUUGGUCACAGUAAAUAAUCACUGCUUUUGACCAAAACUGCAGGAAUGUAAAUCUACGUUUUUCAGUGUUUGAAAGACUUUAAAAUUGCACCAUAUAAGGUAAUGCUGGCUAACUAAACUUUAUAACAUUUGAAUGUAGACCAUAAGCUGAUGAGCCGGAGGUCAAAAUUAGAUAGCUGUAAAUUAUUUGGGCUAAUGAAGGAUAAAGGUAGAGUUUAGCCAAACACUGUUCUUAUGUAGUCUUAUCACCGGUGGAGGUACAGAUGGAUAUCACCCACAGAGGUGUGGGUAGGUUGCUUCAGAAUUAAUUUUUUAAGAAACUGUUAAGUAAUAGAGUAUCUGAAACUGGACUGUGUUUAAGGACUACUUAGUUGCUGUUGCUGGGUAUUAUUCAGUCUUAAGCUUCUUCCUGGUUAUAAAAUUAAAAAGCAAGAAAGAGACGGCAGGAAGGAGCGGGGUGGGGGGAUGGUCGGUGGUUAGUAGAUAUGUGGACCUAGAGUAGCCUUUUCAGCCAGUUUGGGUUGUGAAAUACUGCUGAGUGCUUAUGUGGCCAAGUUCUGUAGUUAUAGAAGAUUAUGUAUACACACUCUUUUCCAUUUUGCAAAAGUGAGCAAAGAUAUCCUUGUAUGCAAGGUGUCAUAAUCCCAUUCCUCUUAUGUUUUGAAAAGAAUUACAUACACCUGCAGAUAAGUUGAGUAGUGCAUUGAGCAUCUGAAUACCCUUCCCUUCAAUUCACUGUUAACUUUUUGCCAAUCUGUUCUCUCUCUUUCUAUCUUUUAUAUUCAUUAGGACACUAAUAAGCACUGCAGCAUUACUAAGCUGUGAGUUACUUUUGCUUGAAGUCAGUGUCAGUUAGGUUUUAGAAAGAUUGUGCAUAUUUUUGUUUUAAUUUGUCUUGAGGGCAGAUUUUGGGCUUAAAAAUACCUCUGUAACUGAAUAGCCAAGCAGUACUUGCCCCUGAGAAGCAGGAAGUGCAGCAGAUUUAGUAGAAAUGCUUGAACAAAUCUAGCGUCUUGGUUGAAAUUGACUAAAGUUCCAAAAUAACUAAACAGUGUCACAGAGAGUAGUGACAGGCAGACUCAUCUCAGAAGCAGUGGCUCCUGUCUUCUGAGUGACAGUCACUUUCAAGUGGCAGUCAGAGUGUUGACCAGGCACACAGAAUAAAGCCCCUUCUGUUGAAGAACUGGCUUAAUGGAGUGGGACAGGUUAACAACAGUUGAUUAAACCAAAACACAACUCUAACCAGGCAGAAACACAUUUGGUCACAAUAACAGGGGGGAUGAUAUCAAACCGGAGUGUUGUGGCUAUGCAGUGAAGUGCGGAAUUAGAGGUGGAGCCUUCGUGGCAUCACUGAGGUGGAAGGCUUUUUCAAGACCAUUGGAUUCAGUUAAACAAAUGAGUUGUAGAAUGGGGAUAAGCUGAGGGAUAAGUAAUCCCAUCCUUUACGGAACAUAUUUUUUGGAGGUGGAACUGGAUACAGCAAAUUACAGCAUACAGAAUAACAUAGGUGCUAUCUUGAGGCAGGUGUCAUAUCCUUGAGCCUGCUGAGGGAUCAGAGUGGACUCUGGAAGAGCUGGCCUUUGAGUGGGGCUGUGAAAGAUCAGCGGUGGAGCGAAUAGUCACUCAAGCCUGCAACUUAGGGUAUAGGGAGGAAUGGGGUGGCCCACCCACCAGCCCCUCUGAUGGCUUCUAAACAUUUGCAAGCAGCAAAAUCUUUUCCAAAAAUGCUUGUUUCAGGGGAAGUUGAUCACUAGGCAUGGGUAAUAUGAGAAAUGUGACGGUUGGGGUGGUCAGACCUCUUCCUCUAGGAGGUCCAGGAGUAUAAGUUACUGAACAGCCAUCUCAGAUGCUCACAUUGUAUGUUCCUUUUUUUUUUUUUUUUUUUUUUUUUGGCGGGAGGGAGGAUUUAUUUUUUUGAGACAGAAACACAGGCUGGAGUGCAGUGGCGAGAUCUAGGCUAAUUACAACCUUCACCUCCCAGGUUCAAGCAAUUCUCCUGCCUCAGCCUCCCGAGUAGCUGGGACUGCAGGCAUGCACCACCAUGUCCGGCUAAGUUUUUCUAUUUUCAGUAGAGACGGGCUUUCACCAUGUUGGUCAGGCUCGUCUCCAACUCCUGACCUCAGGUGAUCCGCCCGCCUCAGCUUCCCAAAGUGCUGGGAUUACAGGUGUGAGUCACCGCGCCUGGCCUGGUAAUGUUCUUAAGUGUUCUGUGAGCCGCUAAUAAAAAUCACCUUGUCUUCAUUUACAGAAGCAAUAAGCCCACUGUUUUUUGUUUUGUUUUUUGUUUUUCCUAGGAGGCUACAGGCAAUCAGGAAUAAUUAGAUAAGGAUUGGGGGCACCGUUCAUUUCAGUAAGAGCAGAAUCGAAGAGCUCUACGCUUAGGACAGAUUAAGAGACUGACUUCACCCACUUAGGCUGAUAAUGUAAUUUUGGUUUUCUAUGUUUGCUUAUUGCUAAUUAAAAGCAGUAACAGUGAUAGAAGAGCACAGAGGUUUGCUUUGUUUUCCACAUGUAAAUUAGAAGCGUCUGUCUCUGUGACUGUUACUCUCCUGUAGUAGUUUGUAUAAAUGUAGAGCCACAUGCUGUCUGUAUGUCUUGGCUGUUCUCUUGAAAUACCCAGUAGUGCUGCCCAAAUGGCCAGCAGUGAGCACCAGCGGCUGCAAGUCCAUUUAUGCAAGGCUGUUGUAGGAAAGUAAGACAGAGAAAUAUGUCUGCUGACAUGUGAGGUCACUAAAGUAUAGAUUCUUUGUGUACUGUUUAGAGAGAUCCACUUGAUAGAGCUGCUGAUUUAUGGAGAAAUGAGCGCUAGUUGCCUUCCACCCGUGUGGCUGUAACCUUCUGUUGCUGUGGUUGUUAACAGUCCCCAUGUUGAGCAGGAGCAUGCAGAGUUUGCCCUACGCUUUCAGAGCCUCACUUAGUUAAGGCACUUUUGGUUGCUGGAGCAAAAAAGGAAAUUUAUUUUCAGAAUAAAGAAUCCUCUGAGCUAACCCGAGGGAAGGUGGUAUAACCCCACCUCACCCCAAGAGGAACUGCUGCGAGUGGGAACAGGCAAGCCCCAGCAAAGCUGCUCCAAGUUUGUUUCUGUUUCCUGUUUCUCCCUAGGGGUCGGCUUUAUGCCCGCCUGCCUCUCUAUCUACCCAGUCAACUUCCUCUCACCUUCCUAGUUCAAGACAGGAUUGAUGAGCAACCCUGAAAAGUUUCACAUUUCUGAUGGUCACGUGAUGGGUCAGGCCAUCUGGUCAGCAGUCGUCAGGGUCGUAUACAACACACACAAGGCUGCGGGCCUGAACCCUUGCCCCAAGAAGAUUCUGCCACAGAGUUUAUGGCCCCAGUUAAGAAGAUGUUCUUUGAUCACUUUUUGUGACAUUCCCUCCAUAGGUAGAGGUCAGAUCGCCAAAUAAAUAAUAGUAUCUAGAGUCAGGGAUUUUAGUCUACAGUCGAGACCUAUGAAUUUUGGUAGGAAAUAAAUGAAUUAUAUCUUUAUUUUCGUGGAUCUCAAUAAAAUUCAGUAUUUCUUUCAAUUGUGAAUGUAGUUCUAGCAGUAUCUGUGACUUUUCACCUGUGGAUACUGCAGAUAUUUUUAAUCGACAUUAAUUAUUACAGAUCUCUCAAAAUGUUGUUCAUGCUCAUCACUUCAAAACUGUAGAAGUUACUAGAAUGACUGCUAUUUUCAUUUAAUGUGUGGUAAAGAUGCACAUAUUACUUUAAAAUCUUUUGAUGAUCAUUACUAUUUUUUUUAGAUAUAAUUGGUUUUCUGGUUAAGUUUCUCUAUGCACUUAAAAACAGUGUUCUGAGAAGAGCUUCAUAAGUUUCACCAGAUUGCCACUAGUUAGAAAUAUACUACUCCCCCAAAAUUGCUGGUUGGAAUUGAGAUUACAGUUUUCUCUUUAUGGCUGUCAGGAUUUAAAUUUUUCUUUUUUUCUUAAAGUUUUGGGAUACAUGUGCAGAAUGUGCAGGUUUGUUACAUAGCACAUAUACAUGUGCAGGAUUCAAAUGCUUUCUAAAAGGCGUUUUCUAAUUCCUUUCCAGUUUUUUCCACUCCUUACUUAGAACUUCUUUGUCCCUUUCAACAAUUCCUACUUCCUUUAAUGUUUUAAUAUCUAGUAAUAGAUUCCAUUUUUUGUUUGCUUUUUGCUGCGUAAAUUAUACAUUCUUUGGAGCUAAAGAUUCUAGAUUAUUAUAGUAUUGAAAGUUAGAGAUAUGUCUAGAUACAAAACUAGAUCUGGGAACAUAACCCCAGAUGGGGAAGCACCAUAUAUUUUGCAAGCUUGUGUUUCUCAAUGUUAGAAAUGAUGAGACUCAGAAUAAAGCUUACUUAUAUCUACCUGGGCAUUUUAAAUAAAACUAGUUUUAUUUAAAACUAGUCACAUUGAAAAUUACACAAAUAUUUGGGAAACUCCCCUGUACAAUAAUGUAGCCUAUUUCUAACAUAGAAUACUAUACAUGCAUUUAGUGAGAGCUCCGCAAAAUCUGUGCGAGUCAUGAAAAUAGACGGGAUACCUAGACUGCUAAUGUCCUGGGUUGGGGAGAUACACCUUAUGAAAGAAAAGUUCACAAAGUGUCAUGUUACAGUAAAAGUAUUUCCUUUGCAUCAAUACUGAUUUGUGAAGAAUAUCUGAAGGUUAAUGCAUUUGAGAAUACCAAAUAUCAACCAUAAUUCUUAUUUAAAAAUACAUUGUAUGCUAAUUCCUUAGAAAAGCCAGGCAGGGUGGCAUAUGUCUGUAAUUCCAGCACUUUGGGAAGCUGAGGUGGGACGAUCACUUGAGUCGAGGAGGAGUUCAAGGCCAGCCUGGGCAACAAAGUGAGACCCACCCUGUCUCUGUUAAAAACAAAUUCAGUUCAUUCUUUCUUUAAAGACAGAGUCAGGCUGGGCUUGGUGGCUCACACCUGUAAUCCCAGCACUUUGGGAAGCUGAGGCGGGCGGAUCACGAGGUCAGGAGAUCGAGAUCAUCCUGGCUAACACGGUGAAACCCCGUCUCUACUAAAAAUAAAAAAAUUAGCCGGACAUGGUGGCGGGCGCCUGUAGUCCCAGCUACUCAGGAGGCCGAGGCAGGAGAAUGGCGUGAACCCGGGAGGCGGAGCUUACAGUGAGCCGAGAUCGCGCCACCGCACCCCAGCCUGGGUGACACAGCGAGACUCUGUCUCAAAAAAAAAACAACAGAGUCUUGCUCUGUUGCCUAGGCUGGAGGCACAGUCACUGCUCACUGCAGCCUCGAUUUUCUGGGCUCAGGCAGUCCUCCUACCUCAGCCUCCCGAGUACCUGGGAUUGCAGCCGUGUGCCACCACACCUGACUAAUUUUUGUAUUUUUUUGUAGCGGUGGAGUUUCACCAACCAAGUUGCCUUGGCCGGUCUUGAACUCCUACCCACUUGGCCUCCCAAAGUGCUGGGAUUAGAGGCGGGAGCCACCAUGCCCAGCCUCAGUUCAUUCUUUUAAAGAUGAUUUUAAAAUUUAGAAACAUGAACUUUUCAAAAGUAACAUUUUUUGCUUACUGUUAAGUAAAUGGAAAGAGCCAAAACAUUUAAUUUUUCUUAAGUCACAGGCACUUGAAAAUCUGGUUUUAACUUUUCUUUAUGGCCAUUAAAUAUUUUAUGCACAUAUUACAGGGUUGAUAAUAUUAUAAUAGAUUCAUUUUAGAAAUGAAACACUUGACCAUUACAUUUAGUUUUUAUAAGAAUAUUCUUAGGUAAGCACAAACAACCUGUUUUCAAACACUGUGUGUCCAGCUUUACAUACUGUAAUUGGGUUCCAUGGACUCUGCCCUGAGGUUUGAGCGCCCAGGGCACUCAUGGGUUGACAGUGGUGAGCAUACAGUUAUGCCCCAGGAGGGCAGGUGAUUUAUUCUGGAAUUCACUUGAGUGUUGAAAACAGAUUAUUAUUUAUGUUAUAUACGUGAGAAAACUCUUACAAGCCACCACUUUUAAGUUUUGCUUUUAGUGGCUUAUAUUUCACAAGUUUAAAGGGCACUUUUAAAUUUUUUUUGGUAAUCACCGGGAUAUGAGCAGAUGUUAUGAAAAUCUUCUUAUGGGGAUUUUCAAACAUAGAGGUCUUUUUAGUGACAUGCACUUCUGGCACUUGUGUGAAUUUCAUGAUAAUUCUUGGUAUCUGACUGCUCUGAAACGCACCAUCCUAGGUUUGUACCAUCCUUGCUGGAGCUCCUGUUCUGGAACCUGGGUGUCUUCAAGGAUAGCCCAGGAUUCUUGUACUUUUAAGCCUGCUACCUGUGGUUUAUGAUCAGAUAGGAAAUUUAAGAACAACAACAACAAAAAAAGCUAACAGGGUAGAGAGAGAAUAUUGCCGGGCUGACUGGCUUCCAUCCCUCGCUGGGUCCCAGAGCCCAGGACCCCUUGGAGAGGAAGAACCACUCCUCCUGUCUCCUGCCCAGAGGUCUCCCACUUCUCAUCAGUCCCUGGGCUUGGGUGCCUAGGAGUUUCCCUUCUGCCUGUCUUGAGGGCUGAGUAUAUGGACUGCAGGAAGGAGGGGCUGCUUUGCAUCUUCAUGCUAAUGCAAGACUUUCUCUGGAAUUUUCACAGGCCCAUUAUUAAACAGAAAAGCAAAAUCGGUCCUCACCAUACCGUGGCUUGGCUCUGUUUCUAAUGCACUGCAAGUAUUUUAUCAACAUUGUCUACUUUUUUGUUUUACUUGAUUAUUUUAUAUUUAUUCACCAUUUAAUUUAAUAUUACAGAUACUGUUUGUCAUGUGUUUGGCUUUUGUGUUUGCUUUUAACAAAUACUCUUGUAUUCAUGGUUUUCCUUGUUUGUGGAGUAAUUCAUUUUGCCACUUCUUUUAACCAUUCUUCCCUAAAAAUAGUCUGCUAGGGCAGAGAUUCCAUUCGGCCUUUAUUACUUUGGAUUUGCCAAACAAGCAGCAGAAACAGAGUUGUACGUGUGGUCCUACACCACAAGGAUUUUUAAGAGAGGUCAUUUGUAGGUGAUGGUUGUUGACACAGGAAUGCUGUCAAUUAAAAAAGGGGAGAAAAUGAAUAAUAUUCAAAUUUACUGGCAUAGAGAUGUUUGCACAGAUUCCAUGUGAGAGACGUAGGCUGUUAAUCUUGUGUUCUGGCCGCAUGUUAGGAACCCUCUUAUGGUGUGGAUAAAAAGCCUUGUGCCUGCCUGGUAUUAGAAAGGUGACAGGUGUUGCUGUCAAAUAUUGAUGCUUUGAUAUCUUCACAUUUCUUGAUAAGCUGACCGCGUAAUUGUCUAAACAGAGAUGGUGUUGAGAGUGAAAGAGGGUGUUACCAAUAAUUAUUCUAGAACAGUAGGGGUAAACUGAGACUGUGUCUGUCAAGCUAGGAUGUGUGAUGACUCGACCUACUGACUGACCAUAGUUUCAUAAUUCAGUAUGUAGAGGGUGAGAGUCAUGUGAAGAUAUUUAUGACUCCCACUGGUCAUUUUUUGUGGCUCACCCCUAACUUGGAUAAAAUGAUGUUUGACUCAGUCCAGGAUACAUAAAGGCAUGGACAGUUGGCCAAGGAGAGUGGUCACAGGGGUGCUGCUGAGUCAGCACCUCCUGUCAGUGGUGGUCUGUUUGAAAACAGACCUACAGCACAUUUGAAGAAGCCUCCUCCCCAUAGCCUGGAGUGGCUGAAUCGCUCAUUUUGUGUGUGAGCUAAGUGUGACUUGAGCCAUGAAUCAGGAUUUGUCAGCCCCCAGGACCUGGCUUGCGUCCUACCCUUCUUUACCAAGAGCUCAGAAGGGGGUCUUUGUACUCCCCCCACCCCCGCAGAAGCCGGGACUGGAGGGUGGUGAGAAAGCCUUUGUCACCGCCUUCCCAUUUGGAGUGAGGGAAGAGUUUUGGUCAUAGUCCCCUGCUGCUCCCGGCCAGCACGUCGGUGUCCCGUCCUGCCACCCACCCCGCUUUGGCCCCACCCCCCACCUUUGUGGGUCUGGUGUCUCAGAAUGGAGAGAGAAAUCCUGUUUAGCAGUUAGGUACCCUGUGACUUCUUUACCAUGUGCUAGACUCAAACAUACGGUGAAGUUAGAGGAAUUGUUUUGUAUUUGUUCUUAAUUACUCUGUAAUACUACAUUACAAUUUUAAAACCAUUUUAAAAUAAAAAUGUAUUCUUUUCACUUGUUCUGCCCUCAGAAUUCUUCAGUAAUAUAAAUAUUUAAAUAAAUCAACAAAGCUUUUUUUUUUUUUUCUUAAAAUCUGGAUUUUUUUUAGGGUCUCACUCUGUUGCCCAAUUUGGAGCAGUGGCACAAUCACGGCUCACUGCAGCCUUGAGCUCCGCUGAAGUGAUCCUCCUGCCUCAGCCAGGCAUGCAUCACGAAGCCCAGCUCAGUUUUUGAUUUUUUUUUUUUCUUUUGGUAGCAGUGCAGUUUCACUGUUUUGCCCAGGCUGAUCUCGAACUCCUGGGCUCAAGCCAUCCUCCCAGCGUGCUGGAAUUAUAGGCAUGAGCCACCACACCCAGCCUCAAUCUGGAAUUUUACACAUAUUUUAAGUUCAUUUGAUUUUUGAACAUGUAUUGGCUAAAUUAAUGAUUAACUGUCUGGGCAUGGUGGCUCAGGUGUGUAAUCCCGGCACUCUGGGAGGCUGAGGUGGGUGGAUCACCUGAGGUUGGGAGUUUGAGACCAGCCUGGCCAACAUGACCAGUAGAAACCUCGUCUCUACUAAAAAAAUACAAAAUCAUUAGCUGGGCGUGGUGGCACGCGCCUAUAAUCCCAGCCACUCGGGAGGCUGAGGCUGGAGAAUCGCUUGAACCCAGGAGGCGGAGGUUGCAGUGAGCUGAGAUCGCACCACUGCACUCCAGCUUGGGUGACAGAGCAGGACUCCUGCUCAAAAAAAAAAAAAAAAAAAAAAAAAAAAGAUUAACUGUAAUAUAGAUGUGGUAAAGCCUAUGCGUUAUAUUCCCUAGUUUUCUGGCACAACCUCUUAAAGUUACCUGGAUCAAAAGCUGGUUACAUGCUGAUAUUUUCAGUCUGUGGCCUGAAUUUCCAAACCGAUCAUUAGAUGUUGCCUGGAGCUUCCUAUUCUCAUUGGAUUAAAAAAGAUUAUUUUGAAGGUAAUGGGACAAAAGAAGAUAACUGACUUUACAACUUUUUAUAAAACUAUGCUGAGACUUAGUAUUGUUUGAAAUGAAAGCUGUUAGUAUUCUUAAAUAAAUAAGGAUUGUUUGCCUUCUAAAGAAUAUAACCUAAAUUGUUCCUUUGUAAGAAUCACAUUUUUAACUUAAAUAAAAAAGGCAGACCAUGUUGUUAGAAGUGUCUGAUCUUUGCAUAUGAAAAUAUAGGCCAGACACAAUGGCUCAUGCCUGUCAUCCCAGCAAGUUGAGAGGCCGAGGUGGGAAGAUCGCUUGAGGCCAGGAAUUUGAGACUAGUCUGGGCAACAUAGCAAGAUCCUAUCUCUACAAAAAAAUAAAAAGCUGGGUGUGGUGGCACGCAGUUGCAGUCCUAGCUACUCAGGAGGCUGAGGCAGGAGGAUCUCUUGAGCCCAGGAGUUUGAAGCUGCAAUGAGCUCUGAUUUCAUCACUGUACUUCAGCCUGGGUGACAGAGUGAGUGGUCCCAUGUCCCCCCAGUGCCCCCACAAAAAAAAAAAAGAAAUAUAGGUAGGUAGGCAGUUUUAAUUUUCUUUUGAAAUUUAUGAUUUGAGUUGGCUUAUUUUCUGUAUAUACUAAAAUAUUUAAUUUUGUCUAGGGAAAUCCUUCAGAAAAAAGUUAAGGUAUAAAGAACAUGCAAGAAAAUUGUGUUCAUAAACAUUCACAUUUAGAAUUUUCCUUGUUUCCAUUAUAUGGAUUAUAAAAAAAUAACAAUGGAAUACUACAAUGUAUUUUUUUUUGUUUCAUUCUUCUAUUAGCUGUAUUUCUUAGGCUCUUACCUUUUUGUAGGACAUACAGCUAACACUGCAGACUUAAAAAAAAAAGACAUCUUAUUUAAGGGAUAUAGAAUUUCUACAAAUACCGUAUUAUUCUUGGAUGCCUUAAAGUGUAUUAGAGAACCAUGAAAAGGAAAUGUCCUUUCAGAUACUGGCCUGCUUGAAAUUUUGUUAGUACUUCUCUGAAGUUUUUGGUGUUUGUUGAAACUAAAAUUGUUGUGGGCUGCUUCACCCGAGCCCAGACAAAUCUGUAGAACUAGUUAUCUGUCACCGUCAUCUGUUGUUUCCUGCCUGGGGGGUCCCUGGCACUGUCUGUUAGAACUUCACAGCCAUUCUGUGGCCUGCCCAAUCUCAGAAUCUGUGAUGGCCUUUGUGCCAGAUUGCAGAUGGUCGUGGGCAGGCCUGUGAGUGGAUGUGGAGCGUUUCUGGGGGGCGUAGUCUGUGAGAUGGCACGUGGGACCACUCACACAGGACCUGUGUCUACGGUUGCCCCCAGGCAGCUGCACUGCAGAAAUCCUUUGAGGGCCAUUUCAGUGUCCUGAAAACGCUGGCUGCCCCCUGCUUGACUUAGAGACCAAUGUCAGGGGUCUGUAAAGGUGGAUUAGAGGAUUGAGGCCAAGUUCAGAGUCUUGAAUGGAUGGCAGGAGAAAGAAGAGAAAGUCUGAAGACCACAUGGUGGCCACGCCCCUCCCGGCCUGGGCUCUUUUGCAUCCCCACUUGCCCUCACUAUUCCUUUUCUGGUAGUUUCUACACUCCGGGCUGAUGUGGGUCUGAAAUUCUAGGUCUGACCUCAUAGAACUCUCCAGAAUAUUCAGUCCUCUGUUUUUAAUCUCCUUCUCCCCAUCCCCAUCCUCCCUGACUUGUAUUUAAGAAAUUAAUAUUUUGAAUAUGAACACCACUUCCCACAUAUCAUUGAAUUUCAUGUUAUUACUUUUGGUUCUUCCUGUUCAAAUCUUUGAAGGGCAUUUUUUUUUUUUCUUUUCAUCCAACACAGUAAUGACGUCUCUGAGCUGUGUGGCCUGAAGAUUUGAUAAACGAGACUUCUCUGUGUUAUUCCUCAGGAGCAGGCUCCUCUGGGAAGUGGGAAGGACCCCGGCUCUGCUGUGAGGCUCAGGGAGAGAGAGUGCACGUCCUCCUAUUUGGUAGAACCGCCUAUUACUCCUUGUUGGUUCCCUCUUAGCUGAGAAAGCAUCUUGGUUCCCUGGAUCUUAAUGUUAGUCUUUGGCUCACUCUUUAGAGAUGCUUCUACCUUGGGACAAAUUUAUAUCUGAUAGAAAUUGUUGUCAGAGUGUAGGUGGAAUAGCAAAGUUUUAGAAAUGAUUGCCUUAUCAAAUACAAUGCAAGUUUCUUCUUGUCCAUAGACAUAGCUAAAAAUCUUGUGGUAAUACAUACAUGAUUCAAUGACAGUAUCAAUUCUAUGCCUUAAUUUUGUUGAUAAUUAAAGUGUUAAAAAUUAGUGAGAAAUUUACAUGUAGGAGCUUGGUCUGUAAGAAAAUGCCAUUAAUUAUUACACUUGCUGUACUUUUUCUCUGAUUAAAUCUCAUGAUUUGCUUUUCUUUCUAAGACAUUAUCUGUUGGAACAUUCACUAGCCUUUAAGAAUUCCCUUAAUUUCUCCUGACAGGUGAAGUGCUCCCUAGGUAUGAAUUUGGAGUUCUGAUGAUUUUUAAAAAUCCUUCCCUGAUUUUCCAGAGAUUUCCUAAGGAAAAUUGGACCAAAUACAGUGGAGACCCCCCCCCCUCCACUUUGCCGUGCACUUUGUUCUAGAGCAAGGGUGGCAGCUACAGGCAUUUGCGUGCCCCUGCCUGCAGGCCUGGCUGUAGCGCAUCAUCCUUUGUGCUCCCUUUCCUCUGAGCUGGGCCAGGGCCCCAUCCUUUUCCGCAGGCCUCUGGGCAGCACCAGGUAGACAACAGUGCAUCUCUAGGAUGGGGCCAGCUGCUCCAUGAGCUGGGGAGGUGGGGUCUUCGUUAGGGUUCAGAAGGAUGCCUGUUCCUUCUGGCCUCCUGGGGCUAACUCCUUAUCACAGCUAGGUUUGUUCCCGGUGGCCUGGACUUUUACAGAAGCUACAACCUUAGUGAGGCUUUCCCUUGCUCCCCUCCGUUGAAAGUCUCUGAACUGCAGUUCUGUGGGACGUAUGUUGUGCCCUUGGGAGUCAUUUUUUUGUGACUUCUCUCCAUCAGCAAGAUUGUGAUGUAAGCAGGGGCUUUUCUCUCCCCUUCCUUUAAUAGUAAGUAUGCAGUAAACAUAUGUAUGUUUACAUAAUGAAAAAAUAUGUCCUUGGAGACUUGUUGCUUUAAAAGAUGCUUAAAAGGGAUCAGUUUGUUAAAGUACUCUUUCAGAAUAAUUAUUGCAUCCCCUAAAAAUGUAAACAAAUAAAGUAUUACUUUCUUUGACUAAAAUUGAAAACAAUAAACUCCUCCCUUCCCCCCCAAGAAAAGCCCUAAAGAAACUCUGAGUAAUUAAAAAGAGAAAAAAACAGAAAAGAAUUUAACAUUGCUAUUUAACCAUCAGAGUCUCAUUUUUUUCCCCCUCCAUAAUGGGUUUGGUUUCAGACUUGGAUCAAAAACUGGAACAAAACUUUCUGUGCUGUUUCUGCCCCUCCCGUUUGCUGAGGAGGGAAGGCAUGCGGCCGCAGUUACAGCAUGCUGGCUGCUCCUCACUGCCCAUUUGGGAUAUCUAGAGGUUGUUUGUUGGUGUUCUGGGAUCCUGAGGGACACUGCCAACUGUUAACCUUUGGCAGAUAGUGACUGUUUUACUUCGAUUUUAUUUUCGUGGUAACCGUUUUUUAAAAAAGAUUAAUAAAUUACCCAAGAGGACAUGGCAGAAGGGUUUCGAAAAAACGAUGAAAUGAAAGCUAUGGAUGUUUUACCAAUUUUGAAGGAAAAAGUUGCAUACCUUUCAGGUGGGAGAGAUAAACGUGGAGGUCCCAUUUUAACGUUUCCGGCCCGCAGCAAUCAUGACAGAAUACGACAGGAGGAUCUCAGGAGACUCAUUUCCUAUCUAGCCUGUAUUCCCAGCGAGGAGGUCUGCAAGCGUGGCUUCACGGUGAUCGUGGACAUGCGUGGGUCCAAGUGGGACUCCAUCAAGCCCCUUCUGAAGAUCCUGCAGGAGUCCUUCCCCUGCUGCAUCCAUGUGGCCCUGAUCAUCAAGCCAGACAACUUCUGGCAGAAACAGAGGACUAAUUUUGGCAGUUCUAAAUUUGAAUUUGAGACAAAUAUGGUCUCUUUAGAAGGCCUUACCAAAGUAGUUGAUCCUUCUCAGCUAACUCCUGAGUUUGAUGGCUGCCUGGAAUACAACCACGAAGAAUGGAUUGAAAUCAGAGUUGCUUUUGAAGACUACAUUAGCAAUGCCACCCACAUGCUGUCUCGGCUGGAGGAACUUCAGGACAUCCUAGCUAAGAAGGAGCUGCCUCAGGAUUUAGAGGGGGCUCGGAAUAUGAUCGAGGAACAUUCUCAGCUGAAGAAGAAGGUGAUUAAGGCCCCCAUCGAGGACCUGGAUUUGGAGGGACAGAAGCUGCUUCAGAGGAUACAGAGCAGUGAAAGCUUUCCCAAAAAGAACUCAGGCUCAGGCAAUGCGGACCUGCAGAACCUCUUGCCCAAGGUGUCCACCAUGCUGGACCGGCUGCACUCGACACGGCAGCAUCUGCACCAGAUGUGGCAUGUGAGGAAGCUGAAGCUGGACCAGUGCUUCCAGCUGAGGCUGUUUGAACAGGAUGCUGAGAAGAUGUUUGACUGGAUCACACACAACAAAGGCCUGUUUCUAAACAGCUACACAGAGAUUGGGACCAGCCACCCUCAUGCCAUGGAGCUUCAGACGCAGCACAAUCACUUUGCCAUGAACUGUAUGAACGUGUAUGUAAAUAUAAACCGCAUCAUGUCGGUGGCCAAUCGUCUGGUGGAGUCUGGCCACUAUGCCUCGCAGCAGAUCAGGCAGAUCGCGAGUCAGCUGGAGCAGGAGUGGAAGGCGUUUGCGGCAGCCCUGGAUGAGCGGAGCACCUUGCUGGACAUGUCCUCCAUUUUCCACCAGAAGGCCGAAAAGUAUAUGAGCAACGUGGAUUCAUGGUGUAAAGCUUGCGGUGAGGUAGACCUUCCCUCAGAGCUGCAGGACCUAGAAGAUGCCAUUCAUCACCACCAGGGAAUAUAUGAACAUAUCACUCUUGCUUAUUCUGAGGUCAGCCAAGAUGGGAAGUCGCUCCUUGACAAGCUCCAGCGGCCCUUGACUCCCGGCAGCUCCGAUUCCCUGACAGCCUCUGCCAACUACUCCAAGGCCGUGCACCAUGUCCUGGAUGUCAUCCACGAGGUGCUGCACCACCAGCGGCAGCUGGAGAACAUCUGGCAACACCGCAAGGUCCGGCUGCAUCAGAGGCUGCAGCUGUGUGUUUUCCAGCAGGACGUUCAGCAGGUGCUAGACUGGAUCGAGAACCACGGAGAAGCAUUUCUGAGCAAACAUACAGGUGUGGGGAAAUCUCUUCAUCGGGCCAGAGCAUUGCAGAAACGUCAUGAAGAUUUUGAAGAAGUGGCACAGAACACAUACACCAAUGCGGAUAAAUUACUGGAAGCAGCAGAACAGCUGGCUCAGACUGGGGAAUGUGACCCCGAAGAGAUUUAUCAGGCUGCCCAUCAGCUGGAAGACCGGAUUCAAGAUUUCGUUCGGCGUGUUGAGCAGCGAAAGAUCCUACUGGACAUGUCAGUGUCCUUUCACACCCAUGUGAAAGAGCUGUGGACGUGGCUGGAGGAGCUGCAGAAGGAGCUGCUGGACGACGUGUAUGCCGAGUCGGUGGAGGCCGUGCAGGACCUCAUCAAGCGCUUUGGCCAGCAGCAGCAGACCACCCUGCAGGUGACUGUCAACGUGAUCAAGGAAGGGGAGGACCUCAUCCAGCAGCUCAGGGACUCUGCCAUCUCCAGUAACAAGACCCCCCACAACAGCUCCAUCAACCACAUUGAGACGGUGCUGCAGCAGCUGGACGAGGCGCAGUCGCAGAUGGAGGAGCUCUUCCAGGAGCGCAAGAUCAAGCUGGAGCUCUUCCUGCAGCUGCGCAUCUUCGAGAGGGACGCCAUCGACAUUAUCUCAGACCUCGAGUCUUGGAAUGAUGAGCUUUCUCAGCAAAUGAAUGACUUCGACACAGAAGAUCUCACGAUUGCAGAGCAGCGCCUCCAGCACCAUGCAGACAAAGCCUUGACCAUGAACAACUUGACUUUUGACGUCAUCCACCAAGGGCAAGAUCUUCUGCAGUAUGUCAAUGAGGUCCAGGCCUCUGGUGUGGAGCUGCUGUGUGAUAGAGAUGUAGACAUGGCAACUCGGGUCCAGGACCUGCUGGAGUUUCUUCAUGAAAAACAGCAGGAAUUGGAUUUAGCCGCAGAGCAGCAUCGGAAACACCUGGAGCAGUGCGUGCAGCUGCGCCACCUGCAGGCAGAAGUGAAACAGGUGCUGGGUUGGAUCCGCAACGGAGAGUCCAUGUUAAAUGCCGGACUUAUCACAGCCAGCUCGUUACAAGAGGCAGAGCAGCUCCAGCGAGAGCACGAGCAGUUCCAGCAUGCCAUUGAGAAAACACAUCAGAGCGCGCUGCAGGUGCAGCAGAAGGCAGAAGCCAUGCUACAGGCCAACCACUACGACAUGGACAUGAUCCGGGACUGCGCCGAGAAGGUGGCGUCUCACUGGCAACAGCUCAUGCUCAAGAUGGAAGAUCGCCUCAAGCUCGUCAACGCCUCUGUCGCUUUCUACAAAACCUCAGAGCAGGUCUGCAGCGUCCUCGAGAGCCUGGAACAGGAGUACAAGAGAGAAGAAGACUGGUGUGGCGGGGCGGAUAAGCUGGGCCCAAACUCUGAGACGGACCACGUGACGCCCAUGAUCAGCAAGCACCUGGAGCAGAAGGAGGCAUUCCUGAAGGCUUGCACCCUUGCUCGGAGGAAUGCAGACGUCUUCCUGAAAUACCUGCACAGGAACAGCGUGAACAUGCCAGGAAUGGUGACGCACAUCAAAGCUCCUGAACAGCAAGUGAAAAAUAUCUUGAAUGAACUCUUCCAACGGGAGAACAGGGUAUUGCAUUACUGGACCAUGAGGAAGAGACGGCUGGACCAGUGUCAGCAGUACGUGGUCUUUGAGAGGAGUGCCAAGCAGGCUUUGGAAUGGAUCCAUGACAAUGGCGAGUUCUACCUUUCCACACACACCUCCACGGGCUCCAGUAUACAGCACACCCAGGAGCUCCUGAAAGAGCACGAGGAGUUCCAGAUAACUGCAAAGCAAACCAAAGAGAGAGUGAAGCUAUUGAUACAGCUGGCUGAUGGCUUUUGUGAAAAAGGGCAUGCCCAUGCGGCAGAGAUAAAAAAAUGUGUUACUGCUGUGGAUAAGAGGUACAGAGAUUUCUCUCUGCGGAUGGAGAAGUACAGGACCUCUUUGGAAAAAGCCCUGGGGAUUUCUUCAGAUUCCAACAAAUCGAGUAAAAGUCUCCAGCUAGAUAUCAUUCCAGCCAGUAUCCCUGGCUCAGAGGUGAAACUUCGAGAUGCUGCUCAUGAACUUAAUGAAGAGAAGCGGAAAUCUGCCCGCAGGAAAGAGUUCAUAAUGGCUGAGCUCAUUCAAACUGAAAAGGCUUAUGUAAGAGACCUCCGGGAAUGUAUGGAUACGUACCUGUGGGAAAUGACCAGUGGCGUGGAAGAGAUUCCACCUGGCAUUGUAAACAAAGAACUCAUCAUCUUCGGAAACAUGCAAGAAAUCUACGAAUUUCAUAAUAACAUAUUCCUAAAGGAGCUGGAAAAAUAUGAACAGUUGCCAGAGGAUGUUGGACAUUGUUUUGUUACUUGGGCAGACAAGUUUCAGAUGUAUGUCACAUAUUGCAAAAAUAAGCCUGAUUCUACUCAGCUGAUAUUGGAACAUGCAGGGUCCUAUUUUGACGAGAUACAGCAGCGACAUGGAUUAGCCAAUUCCAUUUCUUCCUACCUUAUUAAACCAGUUCAGCGAAUAACGAAGUAUCAGCUCCUUUUAAAAGAGCUGCUGACGUGCUGUGAGGAAGGAAAGGGAGAGAUUAAAGAUGGCCUGGAGGUGAUGCUCAGCGUGCCGAAGCGAGCCAAUGAUGCCAUGCACCUCAGCAUGCUGGAAGGGUUUGAUGAAAACAUUGAGUCUCAGGGAGAACUCAUCCUACAGGAAUCCUUCCAAGUGUGGGACCCAAAAACCUUAAUUCGAAAGGGUCGAGAACGGCAUCUCUUCCUUUUUGAAAUGUCCUUAGUAUUUAGUAAAGAAGUGAAAGAUUCCAGUGGGAGAAGCAAGUACCUUUAUAAAAGCAAAUUGUUUACCUCAGAGUUGGGUGUCACAGAACAUGUUGAAGGAGACCCUUGCAAAUUUGCACUGUGGGUGGGGAGAACACCAACUUCAGAUAAUAAAAUUGUCCUUAAGGCUUCCAGCAUAGAGAACAAGCAGGACUGGAUAAAGCAUAUCCGCGAAGUCAUCCAGGAGCGGACGAUCCACCUGAAGGGAGCCCUGAAGGAGCCCAUUCACAUCCCUAAGACCGCUCCCGCCACAAGACAGAAGGGAAGGAGGGAUGGAGAGGAUCUGGACAGCCAAGGAGACGGCAGCAGCCAGCCUGAUACGAUUUCCAUCGCCUCACGGACGUCUCAGAACACGCUGGACAGCGAUAAGCUCUCUGGUGGCUGUGAGCUGACAGUGGUGAUCCAUGACUUCACCGCUUGCAACAGCAACGAGCUGACCAUCCGACGGGGCCAGACCGUGGAAGUUCUGGAGCGGCCGCAUGACAAGCCUGACUGGUGUCUGGUGCGGACAACUGACCGCUCCCCAGCGGCAGAAGGCCUGGUCCCCUGUGGUUCACUGUGCAUCGCCCACUCCAGAAGUAGCAUGGAAAUGGAGGGCAUCUUCAACCACAAAGACUCGCUCUCCGUCUCCAGCAAUGACGCCAGUCCACCCGCAUCCGUGGCUUCCCUCCAGCCCCACAUGAUCGGGGCCCAGAGCUCGCCGGGCCCCAAGCGGCCGGGCAACACCCUGCGCAAGUGGCUCACCAGCCCCGUGCGGCGGCUCAGCAGCGGCAAGGCCGACGGGCACGUGAAGAAGCUGGCGCACAAGCACAAGAAGAGCCGCGAGGUCCGCAAGAGCGCCGACGCCGGCUCGCAGAAGGACUCCGACGACAGUGCGGCCACCCCGCAGGACGAGACGGUCGAGGAGAGAGGCCGGAACGAGGGCCUGAGCAGCGGUACUCUCUCCAAAUCCUCCUCCUCGGGGAUGCAGAGCUGUGGAGAAGAGGAAGGCGAGGAGGGGGCCGACGCCGUGCCCCUGCCGCCACCCAUGGCCAUCCAGCAGCACAGCCUCCUCCAGCCAGACUCACAGGAUGACAAGGCCUCUUCUCGGUUAUUAGUCCGCCCCACCAGCUCCGAAACACCGAGUGCAGCCGAGCUCGUCAGUGCAAUUGAGGAACUCGUGAAAAGCAAGAUGGCACUGGAGGAUCGCCCCAGCUCACUCCUUGUUGACCAGGGAGAUAGUAGCAGCCCUUCCUUCAACCCUUCGGAUAAUUCCCUUCUCUCUUCCUCCUCGCCCAUUGAUGAGAUGGAAGAAAGGAAAUCCAGCUCUUUAAAGAGAAGACACUACGUUUUGCAAGAACUAGUGGAGACAGAGCGUGACUAUGUGCGGGACCUUGGCUAUGUGGUUGAGGGCUACAUGGCACUUAUGAAAGAAGAUGGUGUUCCUGAUGACAUGAAAGGAAAAGACAAAAUUGUGUUCGGCAACAUCCAUCAGAUUUACGACUGGCACAGAGACUUUUUUUUAGGAGAGUUAGAGAAGUGCCUUGAAGAUCCAGAAAAACUAGGAUCCCUUUUUGUUAAACACGAGAGAAGGUUGCACAUGUACAUAGCUUAUUGUCAAAAUAAACCAAAGUCUGAGCACAUUGUCUCAGAAUACAUUGAUACCUUUUUUGAGGACUUAAAGCAGCGUCUUGGCCACAGGUUACAGCUCACAGAUCUGUUGAUCAAACCAGUGCAGAGAAUCAUGAAGUAUCAGCUGUUACUGAAGGACUUCCUCAAGUAUUCCAAAAAGGCCAGCCUGGAUACAUCAGAAUUAGAGAGAGCUGUGGAAGUCAUGUGCAUAGUACCCAGGCGGUGCAACGACAUGAUGAACGUGGGGCGGCUGCAAGGAUUCGACGGGAAAAUCGUUGCCCAGGGUAAACUGCUCUUGCAGGACACAUUCUUGGUCACAGACCAAGAUGCAGGACUUCUGCCUCGCUGCAGAGAGAGGCGCAUCUUCCUCUUUGAGCAGAUCGUCAUAUUCAGCGAACCACUUGAUAAAAAGAAGGGCUUCUCCAUGCCGGGAUUCCUGUUUAAGAACAGUAUCAAGGUGAGUUGCCUUUGCCUGGAGGAAAAUGUGGAAAAUGAUCCCUGUAAAUUUGCUCUGACAUCGAGGACGGGUGACGUGGUAGAGACCUUCAUUUUGCAUUCAUCUAGUCCAAGUGUCCGGCAAACUUGGAUCCAUGAAAUCAACCAAAUUUUAGAAAACCAGCGCAAUUUUUUAAAUGCCUUGACAUCGCCAAUCGAGUACCAGAGGAACCACAGCGGGGGCGGCGGCGGCGGCGGCAGCGGGGGCAGCGGCGGGGGUGGGGGCAGCGGCGGCGGCGGGGCCCCCAGUGGCGGCAGCGGCCACAGUGGCGGCCCCAGCAGCUGCGGCGGCGCCCCCAGCACGAGCAGGAGCCGGCCCUCCCGGAUCCCCCAGCCUGUCCGACACCACCCCCCCGUGCUGGUCUCCUCUGCAGCCUCGAGCCAGGCAGAGGCAGACAAGAUGUCAGGUACGUCCACCCCCGGGCCCUCCCUGCCUCCCCCUGGCGCGGCCCCCGAGGCCGGCCCCAGCGCGCCCAGCAGGCGGCCCCCCGGCGCGGACGCCGAGGGGUCCGAGCGAGAAGCGGAGCCGAUCCCCAAGAUGAAGGUGCUGGAGAGCCCCAGGAAAGGCGCCGCGAACGCCUCGGGGUCGAGCCCAGACGCCCCCGCCAAGGACGCGCGCGCUAGCCUGGGCACCCUGCCGCUUGGGAAGCCCCGGGCCGGGGCCGCUUCGCCGCUGAACUCGCCGCUCUCCAGCGCGGUCCCUUCUCUCGGCAAGGAGCCCUUCCCCCCCAGCAGCCCCCUGCAGAAGGGGGGCUCCUUCUGGAGCUCCAUCCCCGCCUCCCCCGCCAGCCGACCCGGCUCCUUCACCUUCCCGGGGGACAGCGACUCCCUCCAGCGGCAGACACCCCGCCACGCGGCCCCUGGCAAGGAUACUGACCGCAUGAGCACGUGCUCCUCGGCCAGCGAGCAGUCCGUGCAGUCCACCCAGAGCAACGGGAGUGAAAGCAGCAGCAGUAGCAACAUCUCCACCAUGUUGGUGACACACGAUUACACGGCAGUGAAGGAGGAUGAGAUCAACGUCUACCAAGGAGAGGUCGUUCAAAUUCUGGCCAGCAACCAGCAGAACAUGUUUCUGGUGUUCCGAGCCGCCACUGACCAGUGCCCCGCAGCUGAGGGCUGGAUUCCAGGCUUUGUCCUGGGCCACACCAGUGCAGUCAUCGUGGAGAACCCGGACGGGACUCUCAAGAAGUCAACAUCUUGGCACACAGCACUCCGUUUAAGGAAAAAAUCUGAGAAAAAAGAUAAAGACGGCAAAAGGGAAGGCAAGUUAGAGAACGGUUAUCGGAAGUCACGGGAAGGACUCAGCAACAAGGUAUCUGUGAAGCUUCUCAAUCCCAACUACAUUUAUGACGUUCCCCCAGAAUUCGUCAUUCCAUUGAGUGAGGUCACGUGUGAGACAGGGGAGACCGUUGUUCUUAGAUGUCGAGUCUGUGGCCGCCCCAAAGCCUCAAUUACCUGGAAGGGCCCUGAACACAACACCUUGAACAACGAUGGUCACUACAGCAUCUCCUACAGUGACCUGGGAGAGGCCACGCUGAAGAUUGUGGGCGUGACCACGGAAGAUGACGGCAUCUACACGUGCAUCGCUGUCAAUGACAUGGGUUCAGCCUCAUCGUCGGCCAGCCUGAGGGUCCUAGGUCCAGGGAUGGAUGGGAUCAUGGUGACCUGGAAAGACAACUUUGACUCCUUCUACAGUGAAGUGGCUGAGCUUGGCAGGGGCAGAUUCUCUGUCGUUAAGAAAUGUGAUCAGAAAGGAACCAAGCGAGCAGUGGCCACUAAGUUUGUGAACAAGAAGUUGAUGAAGCGCGACCAGGUCACCCAUGAGCUUGGCAUCCUGCAGAGCCUCCAGCACCCCCUGCUUGUCGGCCUCCUCGACACCUUUGAGACCCCCACCAGCUACAUCCUGGUCUUAGAAAUGGCUGACCAGGGUCGCCUCCUGGACUGCGUGGUGCGAUGGGGAAGCCUCACUGAAGGGAAGAUCAGGGCGCACCUGGGGGAGGUUCUGGAAGCUGUCCGGUACCUGCACAACUGCAGGAUAGCACACCUGGACCUAAAGCCUGAGAAUAUCCUGGUGGAUGAGAGUUUAGCCAAGCCAACCAUCAAACUGGCUGACUUUGGAGAUGCUGUUCAGCUCAACACGACCUACUACAUCCACCAGUUACUGGGGAACCCUGAAUUCGCAGCCCCUGAAAUCAUCCUCGGGAACCCUGUCUCCCUGACCUCGGAUACGUGGAGUGUUGGAGUGCUCACAUACGUACUUCUUAGUGGCGUGUCCCCCUUCCUGGAUGACAGUGUGGAAGAGACCUGCCUGAACAUUUGCCGCUUAGACUUUAGCUUCCCAGAUGACUACUUUAAAGGAGUGAGCCAGAAGGCCAAGGAGUUCGUGUGCUUCCUCCUGCAGGAGGACCCCGCCAAGCGUCCCUCGGCUGCGCUGGCCCUCCAGGAGCAGUGGCUGCAGGCCGGCAACGGCAGAAGCACGGGCGUCCUCGACACGUCCAGACUGACUUCCUUCAUUGAGCGGCGCAAACACCAGAAUGAUGUUCGACCUAUCCGUAGCAUUAAAAACUUUCUGCAGAGCAGGCUUCUGCCUAGAGUUUGACCUAUCCAGAAGUUCUUUCUCAUUCUCUUUCACCUGCCAAUCAGCUGUUAAUCUGAAUUUUCAAGAGAAAACAAGCAAACAUAACUGAUCAGCUGCCGGUAUGUUCAUCGUGUGAAAUUGCAUUCCAAGUGAGCUGUGCUCAGCAGUGCUUGGACACAGAGCUGCAAGCUGCGCUGGGGUGGAGGACCGUCACUUACACUCUGCCCAAGGCAGAGGUCGCAUUGCUGUAUCACAGUAUUUUAUUCAGGUUUCUGCAAAAAAAUAAAAAGAUAACUUUUUUAAACAAACAUGAAUAGAAUUUUGCAAAUUUAACGUUUUCAAGAUUUAUUCAAGGAAACAAAAUGCCUAUGUUCAACCACUGGUGUUAAUGAACAAAGAUACUGUGCGUCUCUGGGGAAGACGCACCUAGGUGGCGGCCACUCCCAUGGCCUUGUCUAGGACUCAGAGACCACUCGGCUCUGAGCUUCCAGGCGCCUCGUCUGUGUGCAUCUCACGCCCGACGUGGCUUCUGAAACGUGCAUUCAACCUCAAACUUUUGCAUAAAAUAGAAUGAAUCGUUUUGCUCUGAUGAAAUGUAGGCCUUACUUGUAUAUAAGACUGUUCCUGCCUUCGGUCUGUCAUUUUCCCACCUGCCUCCCCUACCCACCCCCCACCCACCACCUGGGGCUUCCUCUGGGGGUCCGAGGGUCUUCCCAUCACAUGAAGACAUCAGGUUGGGUCCUGCCCCACUGCCCCUCCCCCUGUUCCUGCCCCAAGCCGUCAAUCAGAUUGUGGAGCAGUACACAGUCAGAUGAAAAUACUGUAAAUGCACUCAUUGGGGGUUUUUUGGUUUUACUUCAUAUCAUGUGCAAUGUUGUGGCUUUAACAUUUUAUGCAACUAUUUAUGAAGACCUCUGUUGUACCUGUAAUAAAUAUAUAGAAAAAGCACAUACUUCGUAUGGUGAGCUUUAUGGUUUUGUGUGUGUGUUGGGGUUGGCGGGUGGGUGGGUAGGGUCGUAGCCCUGUGCCAUCGGUUCAAAGAGACUUUUCGUGAAAUUUGUUGGUUUUGAGGACUGUAAAAGUGAUUUCAUACUCUGAAUAUAAAACUGGAUAAUAGGGUAAUGUUUUAAAAUUUAUUAUGCUAUUAUUCAGAAUGCCAAAGUAUUAUUUUUUUUCCCAAAAUCAGUCUGGACAUUUACUACUUUUUAGACUUUUUGACGUUGAACUUUCUGUAUAAAAAUUGGCUGGGUUUUGAGCUUUUGGUAAGAAAUAAAAGCCGAUUAAGCACUGGCCGCCCCGCGGCUGGUACCCAAUGCCCGAGUCACUGUGGCAGCAUUCGCACUGGUGUGGGGAGUCCUUUCAACUCAAGGAGGCUGGGUUUCUGGGCACCCUCGAAGUUUUCUGGAUGUCUUUUUAUCUUUCUCGUGUGAACUGCACUACAAAAGAGACCAGCCCGCUUCCCAAGCCAGCCAGACACCUGGGUCUUGAGCCAUAAACUGGCGUAGUUAAGCUUUGCAGCUUCCAGUGUAUUUUAUUUAUUCUUUUGUUGGGUUUUUGUUUGUUUCUUCUUGUAAAAUUGUACAGAAACUUUUUAAAAGAAAUUGGAUUCGAAACUGGAUGUGUAUUCGUAACCUCAUAAUUUUUAUUUGUGUAUUGUUUCUUUUAUUAUUUCAGUUAAAUUUUUACAUUAUUUUGCAUGUAUAUUUCUUUGUACAGAGACCUUACAUGUUUACACAGUAUGAUGUGAUGUAAAUAUUUUAUUUUGCCAUCAGUUAUUUUAAAAAAUUAAACAUAUUUGCCUGA